GUCCCAUUUUCCAGGUGGGAAAACUGAGGCUCAAGAGUUCCAGCAACUUGCUGGAGGUCACAAAGCUGGAGGCACAUGGGUUGGGAUGAGACUUCAGGCCCUGUCCUCCUGCCAUUCUUCCAUCCCACAGGGCAGGAUGGGUGAGGAGCAGGACUCUUGCAGGCAGAGAUGAGUUGGGGUCCUCAGGCUGCCCAAGAUCAGGCAACAAGCAAGAAGGAACUGUCAAAAGGGAGAAGAUUCUUCCUUAACACUGAACAUGACUUACAUACCAGCAGCCACCAGGCCAGCUGCCAUUGGGAACGCUAUGACCCUCACAGCCAGCCAAUGAAGUGAAUGGGGUUAUUCCCAAUUCCCAGGCGAGGAAACUGAGGGCCUCGGGGGAUGUGAAGCUGGGAAGAGCAGUGGAGCCCUGGAGCUAUGUCUGGACUUUCCUGCCUCCAAAGCUUCCUCCAACAAAGGAGGAAAGGGGAGCAUCCUGGGCAAGCUCCACAUUCCCAGAACAAAACAACCAAAGAUGCAGCCCACAGGGAUGGGUGAACCAGAGCAUGGCAUCCUGGACACAGGGCUGGACUGAGGAUCAACCACAGGGAUGAAGCCCGGCUCCAGCUUGUCCCCACUGUAUUUGCCAGGAGAAAUCCCUUCUCGACCUGGCCUCCAUUCCCUGUCUGUAAACAGGAUAGCAUCACGCUGGGCGAUGUCUGAGGUUCCUUCCAGCCCCAGUGUUUUAUUUAUCUAGUUUCUGGUGGUAAAAGCCCUGGGCAGGGACUGUAAGCUGUGCCUUCCUGUUUUGUAGGUGAGAAUGUGUUCUCUAAACACCUUUAGCAAGAUGACAUAGGGACCGCGGCCUUCGGGCAGAACUGUGUGUGCUUGGAGGUGGCAAGUGGAGGCACAGAUGUGUUUUCUUCUGGGUGAAGGAGUCUCCACACUCCCUCCAUGAUAGUGCCUGGGGCAUGGGCCUCCCUGGCAGAAUAGCUGGCCCCAGCUGGGGACUCUAGGUCUGCUUUAAAAUGCUCUAGGGCUUCUGGAUGUGCUCAAGGAAUGGGCUUAAAUUCAGAGCAGGGAAGAAAAACAAGCCCAUGGACCAAACAAGUCCUGCACCAUUAGAUCAAGGAGACAUUGCUGUGCUGGAAAACAGGAGUCAUUUGUGAGAUAAAUGUACUGCUGGGAGACUUGACCUUGUUCCACCCGCAAUACCGUGUGUGGUUAUUCAUGGGACUUCUUGGGUAAAUCAGCUGAGCUCAGAGCUGCAAAGAGGCUUAUAGGCCUUCCCAUUGAGCAUGAGAAUGAAUGAGUAAGUGGCUGUAGCCAUAAGCUGUCACUGGUACCAACUGAGAUAUGGUGGAUGCUGGGCCCCUGAGGAGUCACAGUCAGUGGGGAGACAAGGAAUGAGGCUGUUGUGCACUGGGCCAGGUGCAAGAGAAUCGCCACCUCUCACUCUACCAAGCCAGGAGUGGGAUGAAUGGGAAGAACACCAGAGGAGAGGGUGCCUCGUGCUGAUUCCCAGGGCAGGUGGAGACAAGGAGAAACAGCCUGUGCCGAGCCCAACACACACAAGCUUGCCUGCCGAGCCCAAUGCAUGCCAGUGUGCAUCCGGGAAUUCUAUCUGCUUUCUGGCCCUCUCCAGGGUUCCUCCGCAUCCUAUGCAUGAUACAUUGACUUGCCUCCUGGCAUCUGUCUCCUUUAAUGACCAUGCCCUUCUCUAGGAGAGAAAGACAGUCUUUCUCAUCUGUUUCUCGGCACCCAGCACGCAGCCAGGUAGAGCGGAUGACCAGUAAGGUGUGGCUGAAUGGACUUGGUGACUACUCGUGUUACUCAGAGAUUAAGGCACAAGCCCACUAAGAAACCUACGCAGGACAGCCUGACGUGGCUCCCCACCAGGGGCUCCCUAUGAGACGCCGCACUGGAUACAGGCUGGUGGACCCCCGCACGUGUGUUCUGUUCUCAAAUGUCUCCUUCACCACGAAUCACCUGCAUCCUCCCACCAGCUCUUUCUCUGCCCCCUUCUGAGGCUCCUUCAGCAGUUGGCUGCUCCGAAUAUUAAAAAUCCAGGCAGGAAUUUGCCCACAAAUCAGAUUUGGGAUUUCCUGAUAGCAGGAGCUGAGCUGGUCAUCUCCGGAUCCCCCAGACCUAGCAUGGAUACUGAAUGGAAUACUUUUAGAAGAUUCAACUUUGACCAUUUUCAGAUUCUGCGGGCCAUUGGUAAAGGGAGUUUUGGAAAGGUAUGCAUCGUGCAGAAGCGAGACACUAAGAAAAUGUAUGCAAUGAAGUACAUGAACAAGCAGAAGUGCAUCGAGAGGGAUGAGGUUCGGAAUGUUUUCCGGGAGCUGCAGAUCAUGCAAGGGCUGGAGCACCCCUUCCUGGUCAAUCUGUGGUACUCCUUCCAGGAUGAGGAGGACAUGUUCAUGGUGGUGGACCUGCUCCUGGGAGGCGACCUGCGCUACCAUCUGCAGCAGAAUGUGCAUUUCACAGAGGGGACUGUGAAACUCUACAUCUGUGAGCUGGCACUGGCCCUGGAGUAUCUUCAGAGGUACCACAUCAUCCACAGAGACAUCAAGCCAGACAAUAUCCUGCUGGAUGAACACGGACAUGUUCACAUUACAGACUUCAACAUAGCGACGGUAGUGAAAGGAGCAGAAAGGGCUUCCUCCAUGGCUGGCACCAAGCCCUACAUGGCUCCAGAAGUAUUCCAGGUGUACAUGGACAGAGGCCCCGGAUACUCGUACCCUGUCGACUGGUGGUCCCUGGGCAUCACAGCCUAUGAGCUGCUGCGGGGCUGGAGGCCGUACGAAAUCCACUCGGUCACGCCCAUCGAUGAAAUCCUCAACAUGUUCAAGGUGGAGCGUGUCCACUACUCCUCCACGUGGUGCAAGGGGAUGGUGGCCCUGCUGAGGAAGCUCCUGACCAAGGAUCCUGAGAGCCGCGUGUCCAGCCUUCAUGACAUACAGAGCGUGCCCUACUUGGCCGACAUGAACUGGGACGCGGUGUUCAAGAAGGCACUGAUGCCCGGCUUUGUGCCCAAUAAAGGGAGGUUGAACUGCGAUCCCACAUUUGAGCUUGAAGAGAUGAUUCUAGAAUCCAAGCCACUUCACAAAAAGAAGAAGCGAUUGGCAAAGAACAGAUCCAGGGAUGGCACAAAGGACAGCUGCCCGCUGAAUGGACACCUGCAGCACUGUUUGGAGACUGUCCGGGAGGAAUUCAUCAUAUUCAACAGAGAGAAGCUCAGGAGGCAGCAGGGACAGGGCAGCCAGCUCUUGGACACCGACAGCCGAGGGGGAGGCCAGGCCCAAAGCAAGCUCCAGGACGGGUGCAACAACAACCUCCUCACCCACACCUGCACCCGUGGCUGCAGCAGCUGAGCCCACACUUGUUGCUGCUCAACAGGACUGCACUCGUCUCUGCCCUGCCCACCCAGAGCCCCUCUUUGUGCCCUGAUGGUCCCUGUCUCACCCCUGAAAACAUCAGAUGCAGAAAAAGCCCUGGACUUGGAGCUGGGAAGCCUGGGUUCUGGUCCCAUCUCCAUGACUGAUUCACGUGUGACCUCAGACAAGUCACGCCCUCUCUGUGCCUCCGUUUUCUGCAUCUGCCAAAGGGGUUAAACACUUCUGCCCCACUUCAAAUUACAAGAUUAUGGGGAGAACCCAAUUAGGUAGGAAACAUGAAAAACCUUUGAUAUUUAUAAAAUCAUUUUUACGUGCAAAAUAUAACCUUAAUAUUUGAAGUGACCCCCAUUCCCCAAAGCAAUCAAACCGUCAUGACUUUGCAAUUUGGCACAUCCUAGCUUGUUAGAGGGCACUUCCGAAAAACACAGCCCUGACAGCAAAAUAAAGGUCUGAUAUGUUGGCCCCUUCUAUGGAAACAACGCUGCCAAAUCCUGGAGCAAAACCUGAAGUGUCUUCAUGUGCAUUCUCUGGCAGGCCACAGUCCUGAGCUUGUAAGAUGGUGCAGCAUGCAGACCAGACUUGUCCCCAAGGUCUCAGCGCUGCGGUCUCACUCCUCCCCUCAUUUAAGAAGACUAUCCUUACCUUUUAGUUUCAGCAGUCCUCACCACCACCAUAUCCCCAGUGCUGGGAUGGCACACAGGUGUCCAUUCAGAUGAGAGUUGGGUCGCUGAGCAUUGGUUACUCCUGCAGAGUGUAAUCAGCACCCCAUCCAACUGGCCCGAAAGCCCAGACCUGCAGCAGAACUCUCCAACUCUCUAUCAGCUUUCAGGGUUUUCUCUCCUGGGAAGGGUGUAAAAUCAGCUUGUCAGAUUCUUCUUACAGAGAGUAUCCAAUCGGUAUUGGUGGAGCGGCUCCCUAUUUAUACAAUAGGAAGCAUGGGUGCUUAGAAAGUUUAUUUCAGGAGGAAAAUGGGUUCACACAAAAAGCAAACUACAUUCUGGUCUGCUCAGGGAGAAGCUUGCCUUUGAACUGGAAGAUGUUGGGAUGAGCAGGGAAAGCUUAGACUUUGGAGUCAGGUUUGUGUUCAGAAUCCAGCCCUGCUGGCUACUAACUAACUGGGAGACCUUAGGCAAAGCAUGCAAUCGCUCUGAAUGGCAGUUUCCUCAUUUUUAAACAGGGAUAAUAAAACUAAUAUUGCAGGGGAGUUACAGGGUUAAAUAAGAUCCUGUGUGUAACCCCAAGCAUUGGAUGACUCAUAGAAUGGCCUUUUUUGUCAGCAUAAUCGUCAUCAUUAUUUAGAUACUUUCUUCCUUCACUCACCCAGCAGGUCAGUUUUCUGUGCAAACAAACCUGUUUAGGAUUCUUCCAAAUGUUCUUCCUGGGGUCUUUGAUAUUUGUUUGUUACAUCCUGCUGAAGUUCGACUGUGUUUUUAUUUUUUCAUCCAACUUCCAUUUUUCACUUUUUACAUGAUUACUCAAUCCUUGGGGCUGUCCAUGUCAUCUCUUAGAUUUCUUAAAAGACAUUUUAAUGUAUGGUUAGGUUUUAUAUUUUUAUUUUUUAAAAAAGAAAUAGUCAGUGUUUUCCUCCUUUCAACCGAGACUAUUUCUGGAUUGUGUGCUCCUCGUCAGUUGACUUGUUUUGCACACUUUUCUUUACUUCAUGUCCCCAUCAACAACCGUCCUGCUCCCCACCUCCCCCAGGAAAUAAGGGGCCUGCUCCUCUCCCUACUGUGACCCUGGAGGCUCUUAAGAUGAUGAUGGUUUUUUUUAUUGGGCUGAGUUCACGAAUUAGGGGCAGGAGCUGGAAGUCGCCCUAGGAACACCAGAUUUCCUGGUUCUGUUCAAGUUGGCAUUUCUUGUUUGGAAUAAACUAUUUCUUGGA